AGUGCACAAUGGCUAGAGCAGGCGGCGGAGCCCCAACCCCACCCAGUGCGGAGCGCGCCGCGAGCCCCGCCGCAAGCUGAGCGCCUCCGCCCGCCAGGCGCGCCGGCGCCGGGCCAUGUACUCGGGGAACCGCAGCGGCGGCCACGGCUACUGGGACGGCGGCGGGGCCGCGGGCGCUGAGGGGCCGGCGCCGGCGGGGACACUGAGCCCCGCGCCCCUCUUCAGCCCCGGCACCUACGAGCGCCUGGCGCUGCUGCUGGGCUCCAUUGGGCUGCUGGGCGUCGGCAACAACCUGCUGGUGCUCGUCCUCUACUACAAGUUCCAGCGGCUCCGCACUCCCACUCACCUCCUCCUGGUCAACAUCAGCCUCAGCGACCUGCUGGUGUCCCUCUUCGGGGUCACCUUUACCUUCGUGUCCUGCCUGAGGAACGGCUGGGUGUGGGACACCGUGGGCUGCGUGUGGGACGGGUUUAGCGGCAGCCUCUUCGAGAAGAGUUCCAGUCACAAAUGCAUAUAUGAUGCAUUUUGACAUUUACUGCUAAGAUGAAAUGCAGAAAUGAAACCACACAUCCAUUUUAGUAUUCUCAGAUGUGAUUAGAUGUACUUGCUCAUGUUUUUAUGCUACUGACUUAUAAGAAAAAAAAUAUUUUAAAAGGGUAACCGUUAAACAGCUAGGACCUGCAACUUCAGUGCUUCUGGGAUAACUGGAACAUCAGAAGGACAGAUUUUAUUACAGCAUAAUCACACCUCAUUUCUUUCAUCAGCAGUUGUCACCAGACGCUGUUACUUCCUAAAAUGGCGGACAAUCUUCCCACAGAGUUUGAUGUGGUUAUAAUAGGGACAGGUUUGCCCGAAUCCAUCCUUGCAGCUGCAUGUUCAAGAAGUGGUCAGAGGGUUCUGCAUAUUGAUUCAAGAAGCUACUAUGGAGGAAACUGGGCUAGUUUCAGCUUUUCAGGAUUGCUAUCCUGGUUGAAGGAGUAUCAGCAAAACAAUGACAUUGGGGAAGAAAGUACUGUUGUAUGGCAGGACCUGAUCCAUGAAACAGAAGAAGCCAUCACUCUUCGCAAGAAGGAUGAAACUAUUCAACACACAGAAGCUUUUUGCUACGCCAGUCAGGAUAUGGAGGACAACGUUGAAGAGAUUGGUGCUCUGCAGAAAAAUCCUUCUUUGGGGGUGUCUAAUACCUUCACUGAAGUUCUGGAUUCUGCAUUACCUGAAGAAAGCCAGUUAUCGUAUUUUAAUAGCGACGAAAUGCCUGCAAAACACACUCAGAAAAGUGAUACAGAGAUUUCACUAGAAGUAACUGAUGUAGAGGAAUCAGUGGAGAAGGAAAAGUAUUGUGGAGAUAAAACUUGUAUGCACACAGUUUCAGAUAAAGAUGGAGAUAAAGAUGAAAGCAAAUCUACAGUAGAAGAUAAGGCCGAUGAACCAAUUAGAAAUAGGAUUACUUACUCUCAAAUAGUUAAAGAAGGCAGGAGGUUUAAUAUUGAUUUGGUGUCAAAACUGCUGUAUUCUCAAGGAUUGCUAAUUGAUCUUUUAAUCAAAUCAGAUGUUAGUCGUUAUGUAGAAUUUAAAAAUGUCACUAGGAUUCUUGCAUUUCGGGAAGGAAAGGUAGAACAAGUUCCUUGUUCCAGAGCAGAUGUCUUUAAUAGCAAGGAACUCACCAUGGUUGAAAAGAGGAUGCUAAUGAAAUUUCUCACAUUUUGUUUAGAGUAUGAACAACAUCCUGAUGAAUACCAAGCUUUCAGGCAGUGUUCAUUUUCAGAAUACUUAAAAACUAAAAAACUAACUCCCAACCUUCAACAUUUUGUACUGCACUCAAUUGCAAUGACAUCAGAAUCAUCUUGCACUACAAUAGAUGGUCUUAACGCAACUAAAAACUUCCUUCAGUGUCUCGGACGGUUUGGCAACACCCCCUUUUUAUUUCCCUUGUAUGGCCAAGGAGAAAUUCCCCAGGGUUUCUGUAGGAUGUGUGCAGUUUUUGGUGGAAUCUAUUGUCUUCGUCAUAAAGUACAAUGCUUUGUAGUCGACAAAGAAUCUGGACGAUGUAAAGCAAUUAUAGAUCACUUUGGUCAAAGAAUAAAUGCUAAAUAUUUUAUUGUGGAAGACAGUUACCUUUCUGAGGAAACAUGCUCAAAUGUGCAGUAUAAGCAGAUCUCUAGGGCAGUACUCAUUACAGAUCAGUCUAUACUAAAGACAGAUUUAGAUCAGCAGACUUCCAUUCUGAUAGUUCCUCCAGCAGAGCCAGGAGCUUGUGCUGUACGGGUCACAGAAUUAUGUUCUUCAACCAUGACAUGCAUGAAGGACACCUAUCUGGUACAUUUGACAUGUUCAUCUUCUAAAACAGCAAGAGAAGACUUAGAAUCAGUGGUGAAGAAAUUAUUCACUCCGUAUACUGAAACAGAAAUAAACGAGGAAGAACUUACAAAGCCAAGACUCUUGUGGGCUCUUUAUUUUAAUAUGAGAGAUUCCUCGGGAAUCAGCAGAAGCUCGUAUAAUGGCUUGCCUUCCAAUGUUUAUGUCUGCUCUGGGCCUGACUGUGGCCUGGGAAAUGAGCAUGCUGUCAAGCAAGCUGAAACACUUUUCCAGGAGAUCUUUCCAACUGAAGAAUUCUGCCCUCCACCUCCAAAUCCAGAAGACAUUAUCUUUGAUGGUGAUGAUAAGCAGCCAGAGGCUCCUGGAACCAAUAAUGUAGUAAUGGCCAAACUAGAAUCCUCUGAGGAAAGCAAAAACCUAGAAAGCCCAGAGAAGCACCUUCAAAAUUAGAAAAGAGCAAUCUCGAAAUGCUGUUUUGGACCUCCUUCAUGGCAUCAGAAUUUUCUCAUUUAAAGGACAGUUUCCCAUAUGAGUAAUUAGAAGUGGUUAUAUAUGAUGAAUGCUAUGCAGAUGUUGUCUUUAACUCUCAGACAUUCAGCAUUGAAUAUCUUUGUUAACCUAUCAAUGAGUGAUUUAUUGAUUAUUGAACAUUUUGUUUAGAAUGGGCUAUAUGACCCAGAAUCUUAAAACAGAGUUAGCUUUAUUUUAGUAUUGGGUAUAUAUGUAAGGGUUCCAUAUUAGCAACUCAGCUUAAAGGUAAUGUAUUUGCUAAUGAUCUUCAGAUUUUAUCUUUGUCUACAGAACAAUUAGUAAUACCCAAGUAAUAUUUUAAUUACUUUUGCAGCUGUUACAGUUGCUGCGGCCUGUUCGAAUAGUGAAACAUACACAAAUGGUAAAUUAUGUGGAUCUUUUGCAUAUAAUAUAAAUGUAUAGACAUGGUGGUAGGAAUAGCAACUAAUACAAAUGCCAAUAUGAUAAUAAAAUACAUUUGUCUAUAAUCGUUUAAAGAUUAGCUUUGCAUGAUCCUUUAUGCACUGUGAAGGUCUGAAGUUUAUAAUACUCACUUGACCCUUGUAACUGAUGAGGCAAUGAUGCCACCACAGUAUUCUAAUUUACAAAAAGAAUUGGAGUUCAAUUAGUGGUUGUAAAGCUCAUUUUGGGGAGGUUGAUUGCAAAGGAAAUUUGAAAGAUAAGAUUUAUUCUUAUUUAAUACUUCAGAAAAUUUCUGCAGAGCCCUGCCCUGGCACUUAAAAUAGCUUCCAAUAAGUAACUUAGACCAAAAGGAAAAAUGAAGUGCCCCAGGAGAAGAUACUUCAGAAGGGCUGUUCUGAAAUUCCUAAGGAGGAAUUCUUAGGAAUUCCUAAGGAGAAACAGAGUGAGGCCUUUUUAACCUGAGAUUACAGAUACUUAUAAAACCCUCUAUAAAUAGAUUACCCAAGGUUUUUCAGUGAGAAUGAAACAUACCACCUUGUUGGCUCUACCACUUUAAUUAAUAUCACUAUAACAUAACUGAUAGGAAUGAAUCAAAGGAGGAUUUACCAUGCCCUUUCGGUUGUGUCCCACUUAACAAAUUGUGAAGUAACAAUUUUCUGUAAUCUCUCUUGCCUCUUAGCUGUUAUCCAGAGUAUAGAAACUUUUUUUCUCCCAGAGCCACCCAACGUCAUAAAACUGGUAGUACUCUAAUGGUGAAAACCUGUGGAGCUGUCAGAAGACAUGAACUUGCUUUUCCUCUAGUCCAGUUUCCAUUCUUCAGUCAGAGUAUGAUGAUCCCUGUGACAGUUUUUGCUCUGAAAUAGUAUUUAUCAUGUGUUUGGUACCUAGUAUUAUGCUUUCUCAUGACAGUUUCUCAACAAUCCUGUGAGGCAAAUUCGCAUGUACCCUCUGUAUUAGUGUGUUCUCAUGCUGUUGAUAAAGACACACCUGAGAUGGUAAUUUGUAAAGAAAAAGGUUUAAUGGACUCACAGUUCCAUGUGGCUGGGGAGGCCUCACAAUCAUGGUGGAAGGUGAAAGGCACGUCUUACAUGGCGGUGGACAAGAGAGAAUGAGAACUAAGUGAAAAGGGAAACCCUUUUAAAACCAUCAGAUAUCGUGAGACUUAUUUACUACCAUGAGAACAGUAUGGGGGAAACAACUCCAUGAUUCAGUUAUCUCCCACCAGGUUCCUCCCACAACACGUGGGAAUUAUAGGAGCUACAAUUCAAGAUGAGAUUUGAGUGGGAACACAGCCAAACCAUAUCACCUUCAAAGAAGAAAUAAGAGAAUUAUUAGUAAUUUGCUCAGAAUCUGGUAUGUGGAAGAGCCAACAUGGGGACCCAGCCUUUUGUGAUUCUAAAACCUUUGAUCUUUCUACUAACAUUCACUGUUAGAGAGUGUAGGCGCUGCAGGAGAAAGAGAAAGUGCCCACGAAAAUUAGUCUAGCAUUGCCGGGGGUAAAAAGCACACACUGGUCCUGCAGCUUAUUGAAUCAGAGAAAUGUGAAGAUAAGAUGAACUAAACAAACAUAUUUUAGAGCAUGGAUCUCGAAGCAGAAUUUGGCUAAAUUUUAACAAAAUGUUCUUCAGUAACACAUCUCAUGAUCUGAAGAUUGUGUUACAAAAAAUAUUAUCAGGCCAAAAUUUGUUCGGAAUACACUAAUUUUUGCUCCUCUAUAUGUGAGGAAAAUGAGACUAGACAGAUUUAAGUAAUUGACAACUUACUUAAAGUAGCAAAGUCAUGGAUUGUAUUGACUUUUAAAAAUAUAGUAAAAGUCAUAUUUAAACUUUAUCCUAAAGUUUAAAUCUAACAGAACAACUGAAAUACUUGAAAUAGACCUAUAAAAUAGUAAUUAAAAUGAGAAAUACAUAAGAUGAUAAAUAAAAUGAAGGUGAAGGUAUUCCAGAUCUACCGAAAAGAUUUUCAGUAUCACAGAUUAUUCAUAAGAAAUUGAGAAAAGGAACAAUCAGAAGUUGCAAAAGAUGGUAUAGCCGAAUAUAAUGGAAAUAGGAAAAAUUAGUCGAAAAUAAAGGUUGAUUUAGAAAUGAAGAAAAUGAAUAUAUUUCUUAAUACAAAAUAAGUGGGAAAUGAGAAGUUAUACCAAUAAAAAGCAUUUAAAAAUUUAGGGGAUAUUGUAACCCAGUAUAAUUUUCUGACAGGUUGGACUUUGACCCUAAUGGACUUACUGGUGAACUUUUUCAAAUGUUUAAAUAAUGUCUAUCCAUGUAUCAUGAAGGACAGUAUGCUUCAAAUUGUCUUUUGAGGCAGACAUGUUCUCAGUACUAAAAGACAUUUUUAGAAGGAUUUUAUUCUCAACAGAUGCAAAAUGCAAAAUAAAAUAUUGGCAAACAAUACAGCAACAAAUAAUUUACUAUCACUCAGGAUUAUAAGGCUGGUGUUAAGCAGAACAGCCAUUAAAUCAGCAUCAAAAGAACAAAUAGUAAAAUCCAAAGUAUUAAUUACAGAUAACUUUUCAAAAAUUCAUCAUUCACCCUUGAUUUAAUUAUUUCUCUGGCAAUGAUUUAAUAGACUUCUCGGAGUCUGUUAAGUACUUAAACCAAGAACUACCAUUAUUCCUACUGGGAAAACAUAAACAUUUCUCAAGUGGAAAGUAAACAGUGUUGGCACUAUUUUUAUAUAUGGUUAAAGAGACCUGUCAUUGCAAUAAAAGCCAGCAUUCACAAAAUGAGGAAGAUAAGGAAAGUAGCAUAAAUAUUUUCUAUUAACAUGGCUUUACAACUGCUAAAACUUAUAGUAUAAAAAUGUACUAACAAAGACUAAUUCAAGAAGUUGCAGGAUACACAAUUUUUAAAAAUCUCAUUUCUACAUCUUAGCAGUGACAAACUGCAAUUUAAAAAGUGUGUUUGGUUAUUAAUAUAUAUGAGACUUUUAAAGAAAGUUAUAUAACUACAUAGAGAUAAAUUAAGAAAGAUGCCUAAAUAGAAGCAAGUUUAAAGAGCUAUAUUUUUAAACAUGAACAAACUCCCAUGGGAGCCAUGCCAGUGUAGUGGAAAAGUAGUACAUGGGGAGAUGGGGAGUUUUUUUGAAAACCAGAAUUACAGUUCUCAUUUCACUACUUACCAGUUGUAUACUCUUGGGAAAGUCACUCCUAGUAUCUAUUUCACCAUCUACAGAAGAGAAAUACUUCACAGAAUUAUUGUGGGGAUUAAGUUAGAUAAUGUGUUUUAAAAUAUAAAGCUACAUCCAAAGAAAUGCCAAUAUGUGACAUUAGUAUGAAAUUUACUACAGUUCCAUUUAACAUUCCAACUGGUUGCUGUGUGGAAUAUGGCAUAAUUGUAAUAAAUUAUUUAGGAAAGCAAGCAAAGAUGUAAGUUUUUUUAAUUUAGGGGGAAAAAAUGGGAGCCUUGCUCUCCAAAUCCUUAAAACAUGCUAUUAAGCAACCUUUCUGAAUAUUCUGUGGUGCCAAGUAGAAAGUUUAACUGAAAUUAAUAAGCCAAUGGAAAGAAAGAAAUAUUAAUAACUGCUGGUGGAAAGACUAGCUAGAUGUCAGUGUGGAAAGAUUAGAUCCACUUUACAUGUGAUAUUCCAAAUGAAUUAAAAUGUUAAGUAUAAAAAGAAAAAUACUACAAGUCUCACACCAAUAGUGGUAUAAAGGAACUUCAUGGCAAUUGGCAAGGUAGAUCAACUAAGAGAAAAAGUUUUAAAUGUGUAGUAAAUAGGAAAAAGACAAAACAAGAUGGAAUUUAAAAGAAGCUAUUUGCAUUACACAUGGAUGCACUCAGUUUUUGUAAAACUAUAUGCAUAUCCAUAAGGGUUUGUACUCUUAGGCAAAUUUAUAAAGCGAUCGUGUAUAAAUGAUAUAAAAAAUCAAUUUGAAUGGUAUUCAAAUUUCCUAAUAUUAAAAAUGCAACUUUGACUUAGUUCAUGCUAUUGUAUUAGCAAAACUGUUUUAAUUGCAUGUGUCCUUAUAGCAGCAGCAUUGUGUAUUAGUAGCCUUUUAAGAGAACUGUGUAGAAGACUAUAAAAAGGGCUUUAUAACUGAUCUUUUGACAUACUCACUUUGAGUGGCAUAUGCCCAGGAAAAUAUUUAAAAGAAAGAAAAGCUAUUUGUACAAAGUUUUCUAGCAGUUCCACUCAGAUAACUUUAAGGGGGAAAAAAGCCCAACGAUUGGAAAUGGUUAAGUAAAUUUUGGUGUAUUGCUAGUGCUAUCACAGAAUGUUAUAUAGCCAUUCAAUAAUAUUGAUAUAUGUCAAAUUGUAUGCAAAAAAGUGAGAUUCAAAAAUGUUAAUAAGAACAUAAAUUGUGUUUACUGAUACAUGUGAAAAUUUAGGUCUACAUUGAAAAGAAUCAGAAGAUAACAUGUAAUUCAGUUUAACAUUAGGGGUUCUUUAUUUUUCUUCUGUUAAAUAUUGAUGUAUGCAAUAAAAAAUAAAAGAUUAAUUGGUAAAGUGGUUUACUGAA